GGAAGCGGCCUAGUCCUCCGGCUCCGACAGCUGGGUGUCCAGGCCAUGGGGCAGCCCUGGGCGGCUGGGAGCACGGACGGGGCGCCCGCGCAGCUGCCUCUCGUGCUCACCGCGCUGUGGGCCGCGGCCGUGGGCCUGGAGCUGGCUUACGUGCUGGUGCUCGGUCCCGGGCCGCCGCCGCUGGGACCCCUGGCCCGGGCCUUGCAGCUGGCGCUGGCCGCCUUCCAGCUGCUCAACCUGCUGGGCAACGUGGGGCUCUUCCUGCGCUCGGAUCCCAGCAUCCGUGGCGUGAUGCUGGCCGGCCGCGGUCUGGGCCAGGGCUGGGCUUACUGCUACCAAUGCCAAAGCCAGGUGCCGCCACGCAGCGGACACUGCUCUGCCUGCCGCGUCUGCAUCCUGCGUCGGGACCACCACUGCCGCCUGCUGGGCCGCUGCGUGGGCUUCGGCAACUACCGGCCCUUCCUGUGCCUGCUGCUUCAUGCCGCCGGCGUCCUGCUCCACGUCUCUGUGCUGCUGGGCCCUGCACUGUCGGCCCUGCUGCGAGCCCACACGCCCCUCCACAUGGCUGCCCUCCUCCUGCUUCCCUGGCUCAUGUUGCUCACAGGCAGAGUGUCUCUGGCACAGUUUGCCUUGGCCUUCGUGACGGACACGUGCGUGGCGGGUGCGCUGCUGUGCGGGGCUGGGCUGCUCUUCCAUGGGAUGCUGCUGCUGCGGGGCCAGACCACAUGGGAGUGGGCUCGGGGCCAGCACUCCUAUGACCUGGGUCCCUGCCACAACCUGCAGGCAGCCCUGGGGCCCCGCUGGGCCCUCGUCUGGCUCUGGCCCUUCCUGGCCUCCCCAUUGCCUGGGGAUGGGAUCACCUUCCAGACCACAGCAGAUGUGGGACACACAGCCUCCUGACUCCAGGAAGAGCCAGAGCUGUGCAGGGAGGAAGGGGUGAGAGGGGGGCCCCCACACCUAGACUCAGUAAGGAAGUCGGGUUGGACCUUAACAUCUGCAUUGGACAACUCCACCCCUUCCUUGGCCUUGCCCCUGCCCGCCUACACUCCUACGUGUCCAGGGCUUGGGCCGUGACUUAGGCAGAGGAGUGCAGAGGAGGGUCUGGCAGGGGCUGCUCAGGCCGCCUAGCUGCCCCUUUGCCAGGUUAAUAAAGCACUGACUUGUUUCUCAGCCUCCCUCCAUCUUUGCAUAGUUUCUGGCCCCUCACUUUGUUGCUGGGGCUGUUUCUGGGACCCUCUGUAGGGCCUGGAAACUGCAGGAUGCCUGAGGGUCUCAGGGGCUGGGGCUCUACCUCCCCUGGCCUGGGUGAGUUGGGGGUGGGGCACCAGCACGCCAAGGCAGUGUCCUACUGAUCCAGGCUAUGAGAAUCCAAACAUUCUUUCCCAGGUUUGGCAUUUUAUAGUUAGAAGCAUUUCUGCAACAGCAGUUUCAUGGAACCUCUCUUAGCUAACCUGGUCCAUGGGGCAGCAGUUACGCUCUAAGAAUCCAUGUGGUAAGAUCAUGGUGCGGCAAAUGGAGGCAGGGUCCAACCCAGGUCUUUGUGCUUUUGCCUUUACCCUUGCACAGCUGGAGGAAAUGAGUAGGAAAGAAAUCAAGGUAAAGAAAUGCGCUGGGGCUGUUUGGGCAUCUGUGGAGGGUGGUGCUGACAGGGCUAGGCCUGCACCUCUCUGGCCUCCUCAAGAGCUGCUUGUUAAAUGUUUCCGUGUAAAUAGAAUGAAUAGAGACCGCCAUUUCCACAUGGCAGGCCUAAACACAUGUGUUCGUCUCAGUUUUCUCUUAGGAUCUCUCUAAGAUGAUAGUAAAGAAAAUCAAAAAUAAUACAAAGGGAAAGAAAACAGGAGGGAAGACAGUAGAACACAGAGCCUGACCACAUUUUCUUUUUUCUCUCUGUUGCCGGGGCUGGAGUGCAGUGGCACGAUCUCGGUUCACUGUAACCUCCACCUCCCGGGUUCAAGUGAUUCGGCCUCCCGAGUUGCUGGGAUUACAGACACCCGCCACUAUGCCCGGCUGAUUUUUUUUUUUUUCUUUUUUGAGACGGAGUUUUGCUCUUGUUGCUCAGGCAGGAGUGCAAUGGCGUGAUCUCGGCUCACUGCAACCUCCGCCUCCUGGGUUCAAGCGAUUCUCCUGCCUCAGCCUCCCGAGUAGCUGGGAUUACAGGUGCCCGCCACCAUUCCUGGCUAAUUUUUGUAUUUUUAGUAGAGACGGGGGUUUCACCAUGUUGGCCAGGCAGGUCUCAAACUCGUGACCUUGUGAUCCGCCCGCCUUGGCCUCCCGAAGUGCUGGAAUUACAGGUGUGAGCCAUUGCGCCUGGCCAUGCCCAGCUAAUUUUUUUGUAUUUUUAGUAUAGACAGGGUUUCACCAUGUUGGCCAGGCUGAACUUGAAUUCCUGGCACCUGCCUCCACCUCCGUCUCCCAAAGUGCUAGGAUUACAGGCGUGAGCUACCGUGCCUGGCUGACAAUUUUUUAUUAUUUUAUUUUAUUUUAUUUUAUUUUAUUUUAUUUGAGACAGACUCUUGUUCUGUUGCCAGGCUGGAGUGCAGUGGCACGAUCUCGGCUCACUGCAAGCUCCGCCUUCUGGGUUCACGCCAUUCUCCUGCCUCAGCCUCUCAAGUAGCUGGGACUACAGGUGCCUGCCACCACGCCAAGCUAAUUUUUUGUAUUUUUAGUAGAGACGAGGUUUCACCGUGUUAGCCAGGAUGGUCUCGAUCUCCUGACCUUGUGAUCCACCUGCCUCGGCCUCCCAAAGUGCUGGGAUUACAGGUGUGAGCCACCACUCCUGGCCGGCCAGGAUGGUCUUGAUCUACUGACCUCGUGAUCUGCCCGCCUUGGCCUCCCAAAGUGCUGGGAUUACAGGUGUGAGCCACCGUGCCCGGCCGCCUGGCUGACAUUUUCAAAGAUGGAAAGUGGAUGGAGAAUUAAGAGCUGAAAUUAUGUGUUCCCAAAAGGUGGGGCCAAAAGGCAAGUGGAAUUACCUGCCAGAGCCCCGGAGGGGCUCAGGAACUCCACCAGGACCAUGGAGGGUGAGGUGAGGCUUCGGCCAACAAUGGGGACCGAUGGAAAGUCUAUGUAAGGAUCAGUGGGGUGCCGCUCCCCCACAUCCCACCCACACCCCACCCACAUCAUGCAGCCAGCAGCUACACCUCUGGGUGGGGUGGUGUGACGUGAGGAUUAUUUGAAGGAUAAAUGGAACCAGAGAAGCUUCGGGUCUUAGGCGUACUGGGGAGGGGUGGGUGAGAGGCUAGACCAAAAAAUGGGGUUAAGUGAAAGUCCAUAGAUACUGCUGGGGGGCCUCCCAUGAAAGAACAUGCUUGACCCCCAAGAACCUUCAGAGAAACCCACCCUCUGACAGGCUCUGCCCAUGCCCACAAAGAUCUGAGCUGCUUGGCUGGUUGUUUUUGUAACAGGCAUGCUCUGUUGCUAUUUUUUAAUGACAGGAGGAACUUGGUGUACCUGGCACUUUGGGCUGCACAGACGCAUUAGCAGACUCACCUUGUCCUGUUUCAUCCCUCGCCCUCCACAAUUUCUUAUUUUCUUUCUUUCUCUUUUUAUUUUUUGAGACAGAGUUUCACUCUUGUUACCCAGGCUGGAGUGCAAUGAUGCGAUCUUGGUUCACCGAAACCUCCGCCUCCCGGGUUCAAGCGAUUCUCCUGCUGCAGCCUCUCGGUAGCUGGGAUUACAGGCAUGUGCCACCAUGCCCGGCUAAUUGUUUUUGUAUUUUUAGUAGAGACGGGGUUUCUCCAUGUUGGUCAGGCUGGUCUGGAACUCCUGACCUCAGGUGAUCCACCUGCCUCGGCCUCCCAAAGUGCCGGGAUUACAGGUAUGAGCCACUGCGCCCAGCCCACAAUAUCUUAUUUUCAUGUUUUUUUGUGUGUUUUGUUUUAUUUUUCGAGAUGGAGUCUCUCUGUUGCCCAAGCUGGAGUGCAAUGGCGCGAUCUUGGCUCACUUCCUGGGUUCAAGCGAUUCUCCUGCCUUAGCCUCCCAAGUAACUGGGAUUGCAGGCACCCACCAUCAUGCCCUGCUAAAUUUUGUACUUUUGUAGAGAUGGAGUUUCACCAUGUUGGUCAGGCUGGUCUUGAACUGCUGACCUCAGGUGAUCUGCCCACCUUGGCCUCCCAAAGUGCUGGGAUUACAGGUGUGAGCCACCAUGCCUGGACUCGUUGUUGUUGUUGUUUUUAAUUAGUGAGGAGCUACAAGAACACAUUUAUAAAAAUUAAGAGGAAACAGCCCCACUGCAUUUGAGAAGGUUACCAUUUCCUUCGAAGUUCCUGCUGUUGCCCCUUCCUGGUGGGGGAGACACUGUCCUGUUUCAGUCAUUCCGUUGCUUUGCUUUAUAGUUUUAUUAAUGUGUUUGUGUUGGCUUUGCAUGUUUUCAAAUAUAUGAAUGAAAUCAUGCAGAGUUUAUUCUUUUACAGUUUGCCUUUUCACUUGAUUAUGUUCCUGAGAUGUAUCCGGAUUAUUGUGUGUAGCUGUAUGGCAUUCCUUUUCCCUGCUGCCUAGUGAUCCAUUGAAAAUACAAUAAUUGAUUUUUCUAUGUGGUUCCACUGGUCAUUUUUCUGCCCCUGUGCCCUUUGGGAAUCAUCUCCUAAACUCUAGUCUCGGCCCUUGCUCUUCCAUGUAACCUUGAGAAUCAGCUUGUCAAAUUCCCCCCAAAAACCCCUUGAGAUGUAGAAUGGAACCCAGCUGAAUCUAUAGAUCAGUCUGGAUAAAAUCAGCACCUGUGUAAAAUUGAAUUUUCCCAUUCAUGAGCAGGGUUUAUUUCUGCACUCAAUGUUUUCAAUAAAGUUGUGUACCUUUUCCCAUAAA